CUUGGCCUCCCAAAGUGCUGGGAUUACAGGUGUGAGCUACUGCACCUGGCCUGAGAUGAGAAUUUAAAAUAAUGCUUUGGGUUCUGUGAUCUAGACAACAAUUUCUUUUGUUGCUAAUUAGAUGAAAGGUAUAGAAAGUAAAAUGAUUGGGCCCCCGGAGAAGCAGGAUUUUCCCCAGGGAAUCCAACAAAUCCAGAGAAUGUCUUUGUUACGGGAGGAUUGUUGUUUUAGUUAAAGAUGUGCUUUGGAAAUGUCUUCUUCCUUCAUGUUAGUAUCAUGAUCAUUAUCAUGUUAAAAAAAAAAAAAAAAUUUACAAACCACCUGGCCACCCAGAGCAGAAUUACAGUCAGCACUCUGUUUCCCCAGGUCCUGAAUCCUUGGAUUCAACCAACCUCAGCACUCUGUUUCCCCAGAUCCUGAAUCCUUGGAUUCGACCUUGGGCGGGGGAAAAAGAGUGGUUGCUUCUGUACUGAAUAUGUACAGGCUUUUUUUUUUUCUUGGCAUUAUUCCCUAAGGAAUACAGCAUAACAACUGUUUACAUAGCAUUUACAUUGUAUUCGGUAUUAUAAGUAAUUUAGAGAUGAUUUAAAGUACAAGAAAGGCUGUGCAUAGGUUAUAUGCAAAUACUACAUCAUGUUAUAUCAGGGACUUAUGCAUUUGUGGACUUUGUAUCCUCAGAGGUCCUGGAACUCAUCCCUGGAACAGGGACGACUGUACUUAAUACGCUGUCCAAAAUGAAUUGGACUGCCAGCAUUCUCUACUUUUUCAUGUAUUACUCUUAGGUCAGGGGAAAAAACAAAUCUCUGUAUUUUAUAAUUAAGAAUGAAUCCCUGAGUCAUUUGACUUCUUCAAUGACAGAGCAAGCCACGUAAAAAUACCCUUCCAAGGAAAGCCAUCAGGGAGCCUCAGAAUGGGUACAGUUUCACCCCAUUUACCUAACCUUUUCUGCCAGUGCAGCUGAGCCUCUCAACGCGACUUUAACAAACUCUCUCUGAGCCAGUCUUCUCAGUGCCAUCUUUGCUUUCAUUCAACUUUACAUGUCUAGUGUUGCUGCUCAAACCUGUGUCCCCUCAAGUCCUUUCCCAACUAAAGGAUGGUGGUUAAUUGACAAUAGACAAACAAGUCUCAGAACAAUUAUGAGGGUGUAAUGAAGUGUGCAUUCGUACAUGCAAUUAAAUAGAGGAAAGAUGCAGGAGGGAAUGUGUACACAAUCCUCCUCCAGCUGGCACGCCCUGCCUGGAGGUGCUCCUCCACUGGAAGCCUGUUGUGUGCUCCUCUGGCAAGGAGAUGAAGUCCCAGAUUUUUAGUGCCUCAUGCAAGGUCUUUUCCACCUCCUUCACUAGUUGACUUAGCCUGGCAUGUAGCAAACUCUCAGUGUCAUCUGCCUCCAACACAGUUUUCCCCAGGUCUUUCGUACCUUGGCCUUCACAUGGGAAGCCAAGAGAUGCUGAGCACAUGGAGGAGGGCAAUCUUUUCCCCCUUUGAUUAUUAUUUUUUUAAUUCAUUGAGAUUCUAAGUCCUCUGUCAUUUCAAAGAAAGGAUACUCUCUUUCCUUUGGAGCUAUGUUCUACAUAUCAUCCUAAGUGGAAAAAAAUCAUUAAAUAGGCCGGGCGUGGUGGCUCACGCCUGUAAUCCCAGUACUUUGGGAGGCCAAGGUGGGCGGAUCGCUUGAGCCCAAGAGUUCAAGACCAGCUUGGCCAACGUGGCGAAAUCCCGUCUCUUCUACAAAUACAAAAAUUAGCUGGGCGUGGUGGCACAUGCCUGUAAUCCCAGCUACUUGUGAGGCUGAGGCAGGAGGAUUGCUUGACCCCAGGAGGUCAAGGCCGCAGUGAGACAUGAUGGUGCCACUGCACUCCAGCCUGGGUGACAGAGUCAGACACUGCCUCAAAGGAAAAAAACCAAACAUACCUCAAAUAAUGUCUGCAAAAUAAAAGACUAUGAACGGAAUAUGGAGAAAGCCUCUAAGAUGGCCCCAGGGGAGUGUUAACAUGUCUAGCCUGAUUAAUUGGCUAGUUUGGGAAUAAUUCUAUCCAAAGUGAGUGACAAGGCAUGGCUGGCUAGUGUCAACUUUGUCCUCAGCUAUAGUUAAAGGCAGGCCUGGAGGGCUGACUUGUUCAGUCUCAGUAGCAAAAAAGUGCAUGGUGUCUGGAUAAGCAGGUUGUACAGCCUAUUAGAAAAGAAAGGUAACAGUCUUCCUCUAAUGCAAUAAGGGAUUUUUUUUAAAGUUCUCCUGUCAAGAUUUUUUAAUACCAGAAUCUGAGAGUGGAGAAAAUUGGCCCAAGGACAGACAAAAGAGCUGGGAGGAAAAUCGACUAUAUUUUUCAACACACAAUGCCAUUUGAAGUACUGGAUUGAGUACGGAAGUAUUACGAACAUUCCUAAUUUGGUUAGUGUCUAUAUUUCUUAAUAUAGUAAUGCUAUUAAUGUCUGUCUCCUAAGUUUGUAUAAAUCCAAACCCCCAUGUUAUUGGCCAGUUGGAAACAAUAAUGUAAACAGACUCUGUUGCCCAAAUUAAGUUAUGUGCACCGAAUGCUUUGUCAAACUGUAACUAUUUUAAUGUUCAUUCUAAGCCACAAAUCUUUGCCAAAGAAGAUACUGAAUUACUCUCUUUUGUUUAGGAGUAGAAUACACAAUAACCUAAUAUUUAAAAGUAUUAUUCAGAAGAAGAAAAACUUAGGAUUGAAUUUUUCUUUAUCAUAAAUUUUAGAUCAUUCUCUUUGCUCGAUUCCAUAGAAGACACUAAGAAUUAGACUGAACUGCUUUCUCAUUGUAUUGUUUUCUACUUGACCUAAAAAUCCAGGGGUGGGUUAUAUAGAGAGUUUAUUUAGGAGACUUUGGUAAGGGAGAGAGAAAAAUAAUGUACAAGCUGGAAACGCAUGAAAAAUGUAAACAAUGAAAGUUAGAAGAAUGGAAGCGACAGUGUGCUCAGGAAAUGAUGUGUCAUUUGGUCGGAGUUCAGGGUGCCCCUGAAUCCCAGGAGGGUAGCACUUGCUUUCCUGCCCAUUGUGAAGGCAAGGAAUCCGCGUGUUGUCCUAUCAAUUCCAUUCAUGGCAGGGUAGAGACUUUUCAAAUGGAAGAAAAUGUGCAUUAAAGGACAUUCUUUCUGCAUGGGGUGGGGUAGUGAACGUGUUGGGGUUGAGGCACGGAGUUGUUUAGGUCAGGUGAAUAGUGAGGGGAAAUGGGCAGGCAGUCAAUGGUUAAGUUGGUGUUUUGCAAGCCAUUUUAAGAGGAUACCAAAUAAAAUGCAUUAAUCUACAUUUCAUUAAAAAUUAGUUGGUGGGAAAGUGGAAAGUUGAAGAUGAGAACUUUCCAAGUAAAACAGCUUCAUACUCCUUGGCCAGAACACCACUAUAUUUACAAAUAGGGGAUAAAAACACCCACUUCCUAGGUGGUCCAUAAGCUUAACUGGGCAGGCAUAUGACACUUCUGAGCAUUUGAUGCCGUUCUCUGGGGGGGUUAAAGCCUGAAUGCCCACCAAAUCCCCUGUCUGAGCAUCAUUUGUGACCAAGAUUCAAAUUAUUUCCCAUGAAGCUCUAAGGUCUCAUAUAACUCAGUGGAUGUAGCUCACGACUUCUUCUUUUGACCCCAGUAUUCUAAGACAAACACCACAGCCGAAGCUGGAAGUGAGAGGAGAGGGGUUCGUUUCAGAGUCAGGAGCCCAAGGCGCCCCAGCAAUUUCAGACCCCCUGGGACAGGAACUCCUCCUCCACACGUUGGAAAACAGAAGCUAUUUUCUAUCCCGUGGGUUGCGCUGGAAGAGCUGAGAGGCCAGGCUGUGGAUCCUUGCCACGAACAACAAGAGAGGGCAAGUCCAGCCGCCUGCUAGGGGACUAGCAGGAAGCGGCACGCCUGCCAGAGCUCAUCACUUCAACUCUGGCUUUCACUGCGCUCAUUCCCUGAAUGGCAGUAACCAGGGGGCGGGGGUGGCAUGGGAAAUGAAAGAAAGAGAUAUGGGAAACUAAAUCUGCCGGGGGAAAGAGAGUUACCGGAGUUUUAGCAAAACAGCUAGCAGAUGCAAACGGGGAGGCAGAGGGAGGAGGGAAGGCUGGGCUUCAGCAACCUGCCACGGGGAUUUAAACAAAGGAGGUUUGAGAGAGGCGGGAUCUGGCUGUAAUAUCGGCACAGGGACAGAGACAGCAGCUGGACUCUCGGGAUGAAACGGAAUCGAUUCCCAGCGUCUCCAACAGGGCAGGAGUGAGUGGAGUAUGUUGCAAAAUAAGAACUCAGAGAAACGAGUGAGUUUGGAAAAAAGACUUACAGAUUUUGACGGUCUCUUGACAUUUCACCCUUCUUUGAGGCAUGCCUUUAUCAAUGCGUUACCUCUUCAUAAUUUCUGUCUCUAGUGUAAUUAUUUUUAUCGUCUUCUCUGUGUUCAAUUUUGGGGGAGAUCCAAGCUUCCAAAGGCUAAAUAUCUCAGACCCUUUGAGGCUGACUCAAGUUUGCACAUCUUUUAUCAAUGGAAAAACACGUUUCCUGUGGAAAAACAAACUAAUGAUCCAUGAGAAGUCUUCUUGCAAGGAAUACUUGACCCAGAGCCACUACAUCACAGCCCCUUUAUCUAAGGAAGAAGCUGACUUUCCCUUGGCAUAUAUAAUGGUCAUCCAUCAUCACUUUGACACCUUUGCAAGGCUCUUCAGGGCUAUUUACAUGCCCCAAAAUAUCUACUGUGUUCAUGUGGAUGAAAAAGCAACAACUGAAUUUAAAGAUGCGGUAGAGCAACUAUUAAGCUGCUUCCCAAACGCUUUUCUGGCUUCCAAGAUGGAACCCGUUGUCUAUGGAGGGAUCUCCAGGCUCCAGGCUGACCUGAACUGCAUCAGAGAUCUUUCUGCCUUCGAGGUCUCAUGGAAGUACGUUAUCAACACCUGUGGGCAAGACUUCCCCCUGAAAACCAACAAGGAAAUAGUUCAGUAUCUGAAAGGAUUUAAAGGUAAAAAUAUCACCCCAGGGGUGCUGCCCCCAGCUCAUGCAAUUGGACGGACUAAAUAUGUCCACCAAGAGCACCUGGGCAAAGAGCUUUCCUAUGUGAUAAGAACAACAGCGUUGAAACCGCCUCCCCCCCAUAAUCUCACAAUUUACUUUGGCUCUGCCUAUGUGGCUCUAUCAAGAGAGUUUGCCAACUUUGUUCUGCAUGACCCACGGGCUGUUGAUUUGCUCCAGUGGUCCAAGGACACUUUCAGUCCUGAUGAGCAUUUCUGGGUGACACUCAAUAGGAUUCCAGGUGUUCCUGGCUCUAUGCCAAAUGCAUCCUGGACUGGAAACCUCAGAGCUAUAAAGUGGAGUGACAUGGAAGACAGACACGGAGGCUGCCACGGCCACUAUGUACAUGGUAUUUGUAUCUAUGGAAACGGAGACUUAAAGUGGCUGGUUAAUUCACCAAGCCUGUUUGCUAACAAGUUUGAGCUUAAUACCUACCCCCUUACUGUGGAAUGCCUAGAACUGAGGCAUCGCGAAAGAACCCUCAAUCAGAGUGAAACUGCGAUACAACCCAGCUGGUAUUUUUGAGCUAUUCAUGAGCUACUCAUGACUGAAGGGAAACUGCAGCUGGGAAGAGGAGCCUGUUUUUGUGAGAGACUUUUGCCUUCGUAAUGUUAACCGUUUCAGGACCACGUUUAUAGCUUCAGGACCUGGCUACGUAAUUAUACUUAAAAUAUCCACUGGACACUGUGAAAUACACUAACAGGAUGGCUGGGUAGAGCAAUCUGGGCACUUUGGCCAAUUUUAGUCUUGCUGUUUCUUGAUGCUCACCUCUAUAUUAGUUUAUUGUUAGGAUCAAUGAUAAAUUUAAAUGACCUCAGAUCUUUGCACCAGAUACUCAUCAUAUACAAAUGUUUUAGUAAAAAAGAGAAUUGUAGAUAAUACUGUCUAGGAAAAUAAGAAUUAGGUUUCUUUGAAGAAGGAAUCUUUUAUAACACCUUAACAGUCACCACUGUGCUCAACCAGACAGAUAGUGAAACAGCUUUCUGGGUAAUUCACCAAUUUCCUUUAAAACAUAAGCUACCUGAAUGGAGAAUACAUCUUGUUUCUGAGUUUCAACACUAGCAUUUUUGGCUUACUCAUGGACAAAGUUCUGUAUAUAGUAUAAAGUCAUUAACAAGAAACAGGAUAUGCUUUAAGACAGAAUUCACUGUCUGUUGCUUCAGUAAAAGGACCUCGGGGAAUAAAACAUUUCUCUCUUAUAUGCCAGAAUGUAGGCUGGUCCCUAUGUCAUGUCUUCCAUUAAGAACACUAAAAAGUCCUUGCAAGAAUGGAGAUAUGCAUUCAAGAGAGGUGCUAUCACAUAGAUCUAGUCUGAAGUCUGGAACACUUUCCUCUUCUAUGACCCCUCUCUCCCCAGUAUUAUCUUACUUGCAAAAUGGAGACCAAAUUCUAUCCUGUGAGGCUUUUAAUUGCACCAUAGUAUGCUCUGAGUAGCUUUACACUGCCUGGUACUGAUAGUAGUGGCUCGAUUUUUAAGAGCCUUCAAUUGUAGAUGAACAUCUCUGUUAUUUAUCCCUCAUUCAUCCAUCCGUUCAUUCAUUCAGCCUUCAAUCAACAUCUCUUGAGUGUCUAUUAUGUACAGGACAUGUACUGAGACAAAAAGGAAACAUAAGAGCUUUUUCACUCUAAAAAUCUUGGCAAUAAUGUCAACACCAGAAAGCCUCCUCUGGAGAAUCUUACAGAGUGAUUGUAGUUUAAUACAGGAACACACAGGGCUGUGUAGCAUGAUACCAGGCCCAGGAGAUCAGUAAUUACAAAUUAAGGGUUAAAUCAGAGAUUAUUCAACAGAGAGGGAGAAAGGAGGAGACAGAGGGAGGACCUGUUGUGUUCCAGCCAUUCUGGUAUUCCUUUAUGUAUCUAAUUUCAUUCAAACCUCACAACAGUCUUGUGAGGCCCUUAUAUAAUUACUCCCAUUUUGCAGAUGAAGUAACUGAGGCUUAGAAAGGUUAAUAGCACCGGGGAACAAUUUCUCUGGGUGAGAAUUGGGACUCUGUUGCUGGUCUUCUCAGUUCAUUUCCUGAGGUGGAUUUACUGAGAGAAGGUGAAAUAAAGCCAUAUUUAGUAUACCAGAGAAGGUAGAUUUUAAGAAUGGUCUCAGUGUUAAUACUGAGAAAAAGUCCUGUCAGUUCAGAAAAAAUGUGAAGUCUACUUUAGUAUUCCUGUAAUACUAAACCGUUGAGUUUCUAAAUAUUUAUUUAUUCUAACAAAAAGCAAUUACUACAAAUGGAUGACACAUUUAAUGAACACAAUUUUAUUUUUUUUCUGUAACUGUGCUUGUUGAAUGUCAAUCAUAUUUAAAGGGAAUGACUUUGAAGUAAAACCUUUUUUCUUGCUACUGAAAAAAAUGGAGUUGUUUUGGGUGGUAAAGUGUUAAGGAAUAGGGACAGCUGGUCACACAAGGAACUCUUGAAGGCCACAUGUGAAAACCUGUCACUUGCACAGAGGCCAGUCCCACUAAGGUGACCAGAGUGGGCUCCAAGCACAAACUGCCAUUGGCUAUAGAUGGGACUGUGUCCCCCCAAAAUUCAUGUGUUGGAGCCUUAACCCUCAAUGUGAUGGUAUUUGAGAUGGGGCCUUUGGUAAGGGAAGUUUAGAUGAGGUCACGAGGGUAGGACCCUCAUGAUGGGAUGAGUCCCCUUACAAGACCUCUGGCUUGGGCCGGGCGUGGUGGCUCACACCUGUAAUCCCAACACUUUGGGAGGCCAAGGCAGGUAGAUCACUUGAUGCCAGGAGUUCCAGACCAGGCUGGCCGACAUGGUGAAACCCCAUCUCUACUAAAAAAUAUAAAAAUUAGCCGGGCUUUGUGGCAUGUGCCUGUAAUCCCAGCUAUUUGGCAGGCUGAGGCAUGAGAAUCGCUUGAACCCAGGAGGUGGAGGUUACAGUGAGCUGAGAGUGCCCCACUGCACUCCAGCCUGGGUGACAGAGCGAGACUUUGUCCCAAAACAAAAUAGGUGAGGGGAUAGCGAAUGCACUCAGGGUCAGCAGUGGAGUUUAAAAAUUGUCUCUUUUCAACUUAUUUAAAUGACAGCACCUGAGAAGAGGAACCGUUUUACACUGGAUGUUUCUCAUGUAGAACAAGAAAUCUUUCUGGAAUUGAUGUUUACAUGUCUGUUGUUGGUCAUCUCUCCUGUGUCUUAAAUACUUUAAUGUUGGAAGAGCAUAGUGUUUGGGCUAGUGGGUUUCUGACAGCCCAUGGGAAUGCCCUGAAACUACUGUAUCUGAUGUUUGUUUUCGAUGAGGUUCCAUGUUUUGUUUUCUUGGGAAUAAAUUAAUAUAUUGUUUUCCA